GUUGACUAGGCGCUGUUCUUGCUGGCUGGUGCCCCAGGGCCUGGAGAGGUCUGAAGAAACCUGGGAGCCAGCAGCCCGGGGCUCCACUCUGGGUUCUGAAAGCCCAUUCCCUGCUCUGCGGCUCCUCCCACCCCACCUCUUCUCAGCCUUGCAGCUCAAGGGUUGAUCUCAGGAGUCCAGGACCCAGGAGAGGGAAGAAUCUGAGGAACACAGAACAGUGAGCGUUGCCCACACCCCAUCUCCCGUCACCACAUCUCCCCUCACCCUCACCCUCCCUGCCUGGCCCUGGACCCCAUCCCAGGACCUCCCUAUCAGCUGACUUCUUCCAGUGUCUUGCAGGCCCCUCUGGGCUCCUCCCUCCCCUGGCUUUUCCUACCACUCCCCCUCUAUCGGCGUCUAUCUGUAGGUGCCCUGGGAUUUAUAAAACUGGGUUCCGAAUGCUGAAUAAGAGACGGUAAGAGCCAAGGCAAAGGACAGCACUGUUCUCUGCCUGCCUGAUACCCUCACCACCUGGGAACAUCCCCCAGACACCCUCUUAACUCCGGGACAGAGAUGGCUGGCGGAGCCUGGGGCCGCCUGGCCUGUUACUUGGAGUUCCUGAAGAAGGAGGAGCUGAAGGAGUUCCAGCUUCUGCUCGCCAAUAAAGCGCACUCCAGGAGCUCUUCGGGUGAGACACCCGCUCAGCCAGAGAAGACGAGUGGCAUGGAGGUGGCCUCGUACCUGGUGGCUCAGUAUGGGGAGCAGCGGGCCUGGGACCUAGCCCUCCAUACCUGGGAGCAGAUGGGGCUGAGGUCACUGUGCGCCCAAGCCCAGGAAGGGGCAGGCCACUCUCCCUCAUUCCCCUACAGCCCAAGUGAACCCCACCUGGGGUCUCCCAGCCAACCCACCUCCACCGCAGUGCUAAUGCCCUGGAUCCAUGAAUUGCCGGCGGGGUGCACCCAGGGCUCAGAGAGAAGGGUUUUGAGACAGCUGCCUGACACAUCUGGACGCCGCUGGAGAGAAAUCUCUGCCUCACUCCUCUACCAAGCUCUUCCAAGCUCCCCAGACCAUGAGUCUCCAAGCCAGGAGUCACCCAACGCCCCCACAUCCACAGCAGUGCUGGGGAGCUGGGGAUCCCCACCUCAGCCCAGCCUAGCACCCAGAGAGCAGGAGGCUCCUGGGACCCAAUGGCCUCUGGAUGAAACGUCAGGAAUUUACUACACAGAAAUCAGAGAAAGAGAGAGAGAGAAAUCAGAGAAAGGCAGGCCCCCAUGGGCAGCGGUGGUAGGAACGCCCCCACAGGCGCACACCAGCCUACAGCCCCACCACCACCCAUGGGAGCCUUCUGUGAGAGAGAGCCUCUGUUCCACAUGGCCCUGGAAAAAUGAGGAUUUUAACCAAAAAUUCACACAGCUGCUACUUCUACAAAGACCUCACCCCAGAAGCCAAGAUCCCCUGGUCAAGAGAAGCUGGCCUGAUUAUGUGGAGGAGAAUCGAGGACAUUUAAUUGAGAUCAGAGACUUAUUUGGCCCAGGCCUGGAUACCCAAGAACCUCGCAUAGUCAUACUGCAGGGGGCUGCUGGAAUUGGGAAGUCAACACUGGCCAGGCAGGUGAAGGAAGCCUGGGGGAGAGGCCAGCUGUAUGGGGACCGCUUCCAGCAUGUCUUCUACUUCAGCUGCAGAGAGCUGGCCCAGUCCAAGGUGGUGAGUCUCGCUGAGCUCAUCGGAAAAGAUGGGACAGCCACUCCGGCUCCCAUUAGACAGAUCCUGUCUAGGCCAGAGCGGCUGCUCUUCAUCCUCGAUGGUGUAGAUGAGCCAGGAUGGGUCUUGCAGGAGCCGAGUUCUGAGCUCUGUCUGCACUGGAGCCAGCCACAGCCGGCGGAUGCACUGCUGGGCAGUUUGCUGGGGAAAACUAUACUUCCCGAGGCAUCCUUCCUGAUCACGGCUCGGACCACAGCUCUGCAGAACCUCAUUCCUUCUUUGGAGCAGGCACGUUGGGUAGAGGUCCUGGGGUUCUCUGAGUCCAGCAGGAAGGAAUAUUUCUACAGAUAUUUCACAGAUGAAAGGCAAGCAAUUAGAGCCUUUAGGUUGGUCAAAUCAAACAAAGAGCUCUGGGCCCUGUGUCUUGUGCCCUGGGUGUCCUGGCUGGCCUGCACUUGCCUGAUGCAGCAGAUGAAGCGGAAGGAAAAACUCACACUGACUUCCAAGACCACCACAACCCUCUGUCUACAUUACCUUGCCCAGGCUCUCCAAGCUCAGCCAUUGGGACCCCAGCUCAGAGACCUCUGCUCUCUGGCUGCUGAGGGCAUCUGGCAAAAAAAGACCCUUUUCAGUCCAGAUGACCUCAGGAAGCAUGGGUUAGAUGGGGCCAUCAUCUCCACCUUCUUGAAGAUGGGUAUUCUUCAAGAGCACCCCAUCCCUCUGAGCUACAGCUUCAUUCACCUCUGUUUCCAAGAGUUCUUUGCAGCAAUGUCCUAUGUCUUGGAGGAUGAGAAGGGGAGAGGUAAACAUUCUAAUUGCAUCAUAGAUUUGGAAAAGACGCUAGAAGCAUAUGGAAUACAUGGCCUGUUUGGGGCAUCAACCACACGUUUCCUAUUGGGCCUGUUAAGUGAUGAGGGGGAGAGAGAGAUGGAGAACAUCUUUCACUGCCGGCUGUCUCAGGGGAGGAACCUGAUGCAGUGGGUCCCGUCCCUGCAGCUGCUGCUGCAGCCACACUCUCUGGAGUCCCUCCACUGCUUGUACGAGACUCGGAACAAAACGUUCCUGACACAAGUGAUGGCCCAUUUCGAAGAAAUGGGCAUGUGUGUAGAAACAGACAUGGAGCUCUUAGUGUGCACUUUCUGCAUUAAAUUCAGCCGCCACGUGAAGAAGCUUCAGCUGAUUGAGGGCAGGCAGCACAGAUCAACAUGGAGCCCCACCAUGGUAGUCCUGUUCAGGUGGGUCCCAGUCACAGAUGCCUAUUGGCAGAUUCUCUUCUCCGUCCUCAAGGUCACCAGAAACCUGAAGGAGCUGGACCUAAGUGGAAACUCGCUGAGCCACUCUGCAGUGAAGAGUCUUUGUAAGACCCUGAGACGCCCUCGCUGCCUCCUGGAGACCCUGCGGUUGGCUGGCUGUGGCCUCACAGCUGAGGACUGCAAGGACCUUGCCUUUGGGCUGAGAGCCAACCAGACCCUGACCGAGCUGGACCUGAGCUUCAAUGUGCUCACGGAUGCUGGAGCCAAACACCUUUGCCAGAGACUGAGACAGCCGAGCUGCAAGCUACAGCGACUGCAGCUGGUCAGCUGUGGCCUCACGUCUGACUGCUGCCAGGACCUGGCCUCUGUGCUUAGUGCCAGCCCCAGCCUGAAGGAGCUAGACCUGCAGCAGAACAACCUGGAUGACGUUGGCGUGCGACUGCUCUGUGAGGGGCUCAGGCAUCCUGCCUGCAAACUCAUACGCCUGGGGCUGGACCAGACAACUCUGAGUGAUGAGAUGAGGCAGGAACUGAGGGCCCUGGAGCAGGAGAAACCUCAGCUGCUCAUCUUCAGCAGACGGAAACCAAGUGUGAUGACCCCUACUGAGGGCCUGGAUACGGGAGAGAUGAGUAAUAGCACAUCCUCACUCAAGCGGCAGAGACUCGGAUCAGAGAGGGCGGCUUCCCAUGUUGCUCAGGCUAAUCUCAAACUCCUGGACGUGAGCAAGAUCUUCCCAAUUGCUGAGAUUGCAGAGGAAAGCUCCCCAGAGGUAGUACCGGUGGAACUCUUGUGCGUGCCUUCUCCUGCCUCUCAAGGGGACCUGCAUACGAAGCCUUUGGGGACUGACGAUGACUUCUGGGGCCCCACGGGGCCUGUGGCUACUGAGGUAGUUGACAAAGAAAAGAACUUGUACCGAGUUCACUUCCCUGUAGCUGGCUCCUACCGCUGGCCCAACACGGGUCUCUGCUUUGUGAUGAGAGAAGCGGUGACCGUUGAGAUUGAAUUCUGUGUGUGGGACCAGUUCCUGGGUGAGAUCAACCCACAGCACAGCUGGAUGGUGGCAGGGCCUCUGCUGGACAUCAAGGCUGAGCCUGGAGCUGUGGAAGCUGUGCACCUCCCUCACUUUGUGGCUCUCCAAGGGGGCCAUGUGGACACAUCCCUGUUCCAAAUGGCCCACUUUAAAGAGGAGGGGAUGCUCCUGGAGAAGCCAGCCAGGGUGGAGCUGCAUCACAUAGUUCUGGAAAACCCCAGCUUCUCCCCCUUGGGAGUCCUCCUGAAAAUGAUCCAUAAUGCCCUGCGCUUCAUUCCCGUCACCUCUGUGGUGUUGCUUUACCACCGCGUCCAUCCUGAGGAAGUCACCUUCCACCUCUACCUGAUCCCAAGUGACUGCUCCAUUCGGAAGGCCAUAGAUGAUCUAGAAAUGAAAUUCCAGUUUGUGCGAAUCCACAAGCCACCCCCGCUGACCCCACUUUAUAUGGGCUGUCGUUACACUGUGUCUGGGUCUGGUUCAGGGAUGCUGGAAAUACUCCCCAAGGAACUGGAGCUCUGCUAUCGAAGCCCUGGAGAAGACCAGCUGUUCUCGGAGUUCUACGUUGGCCACUUGGGAUCAGGGAUCAGGCUGCAAGUGAAAGACAAGAAAGAUGAGACUCUGGUGUGGGAGGCCUUGGUGAAACCAGGAGAUCUCAUGCCUGCAACUACUCUGAUCCCUCCAGCCCGCAUAGCCGUACCUUCACCUCUGGAUGCCCCGCAGUUGCUGCACUUUGUGGACCAGUAUCGAGAGCAGCUGAUAGCCCGAGUGACAUCGGUGGAGGUUGUCUUGGACAAACUGCAUGGACAGGUGCUGAGCCAGGAGCAGUACGAGAGGGUGCUGGCUGAGAACACGAGGCCCAGCCAGAUGCGGAAGCUGUUCAGCUUGAGCCAGUCCUGGGACCGGAAGUGCAAAGAUGGACUCUACCAAGCCCUGAAGGAGACCCAUCCUCACCUCAUUAUGGAACUCUGGGAGAAGGGCAGCAAAAAGGGACUCCUGCCACUCAGCAGCUGAAGUAUCAACACCAGCCCUUGACCCUUGAGUCCUGGCUUUGGCUGACCCUUCUUUGGGUCUCAGUUUCUUUCUCUGCAAACAAGUUGCCAUCUGGUUUGCCUUCCAGCACUAAAGUAAUGGAACUUUGAUGAUGCCUUUGCUGGGCAUUAUGUGUCCAUGCCAGGGAUGCCACAGGGGGCCCCAGUCCAGGUGGCCUAACAGCAUCUCAGGGAAUGUCCAUCUGGAGCUGGCAAGACCCCUGCAGACCUCAUAGAGCCUCAUCUGGUGGCCACAGCAGCCAAGCCUAGAGCCCUCCGGAUCCCAUCCAGGCGCAAAGAGGAAUAGGAGGGACAUGGAACCAUUUGCCUCUGGCUGUGUCACAGGGUGAGCCCCAAAAUUGGGGUUCAGCGUGGGAGGCCACGUGGAUUCUUGGCUUUGUACAGGAAGAUCUACAAGAGCAAGCCAACAGAGUAAAGUGGAAGGAAGUUUAUUCAGAAAAUAAAGGAGUAUCACAGCUCUUUUAGAAUUUGUCUAGCAGGCUUUCCAGUUUUUACCAGAAAACCCCUAUAAAUUAAAAAUUUUUUACUUAAAUUUAAGAAUUAAAAAAAUACAAAAAAGAAAAAAUGAAAAUAAAGGAAUAAGAAGUUACCUACUCCA